AGGUUAAAGCUACCGGGACGGGUCCCGGCAUCUCUAAAUCACCGCUCCCUGGCCUCUUCGGCCUCCGUCCGCCGCGGCCCAGGGGCCGGGCUUCUCAGCUGCUGACCUACUGCCACCGACUGCGCUCUCUCCCGUGGGUCGGCUUUUUGCUCGCCAUGCCUCCGCCGCAGGGUGACGUGACCGCCUUGUUCCUGGGGCCUCCGGGCUUGGGGAAGUCCGCGCUGAUCGCAGCGCUGUGCGACAAGGAUGUGGAGACGCUCGAGGCCCCCGAGGGACGGCCGGACUCCGGGGUUCCCAGCCUAAGAGCUGCGGGCCCAGGCCUUUUUCUGGGCGAGCUGAGCUGCCCACCCGCAGCGCCGGGGCCCUGGGCGGCGGAAGCCAACGUGCUGGUACUGGUGCUGCCCGGACCCGAGGGGAACGGGGAACCGUUGGCUCCAGCCCUGGGAGAGGCAGCGCUGGCCGCCCUGGCCCGAGGGACCCCGCUACUGGCUGUGCGGAACCUCCGUCCUGGGGAUUCACAGACUGCCGCCCAGGCCCGUGAUCAGACAGCAGCUCUGCUGAACAGCGCGGGGUUAGGAGCUGCGGAUCUGUUUGUGCUACCGGCGAACUGCGGCAGCAGCGACGGCUGCGAGGAGCUAGAGCGCCUCCGGGCGGCGCUGCAGAGCCAGGCAGAAGCGCUGCGGAGGCUCCUGCCACCGGCGCAGGAUGGCUUCGAGGUGUUGGGUGCAGCAGAGCUAGAGGCUGUGCGUGAGGCCUUUGAGACCGGCGGCCUUGAGGCUGCGCUGUCGUGGGUGCGCUCAGGCCUGGAGCGCCUGGGCAGCGCACGGCUAGACCUGGCCGUGGCUGGCAAGGCUGACGUGGGCCUUGUGGUGGACAUGCUGCUUGGAUUGGAUCCUGGCGACCCAGGCGCUGCGCCUGCUUCGGUCCCCACAGCACCCACUCCCUUCCCAGCCCCAGAGCGCCCGAAUGUGGUGCUCUGGACCGUGCCUCUGGGCCACACGGGCACUGCCACCACCGCGGCCGCCGCCUCUCACCCAACGCACUACGACGCCCUCAUCCUCGUCACCCCUGGGGCCCCCACUGAGAAGGACUGGGCCCAGGUCCAGGCCUUGCUGCUACCAGAUGCGCCUCUUGUCUGCGUGCGCACAGACGGCGAGGGCGAGGAUCCGGAGUGUCUGGGAGAAGGCAAGAUGGAGAAUCCCAAGGGCGAGAGCUUAAAGAACGCAGGUGGAGGGGGAUUGGAGAAUGCACUCAGUAAGGGAAGGGAGAAAUGUAGCGCUGGAUCGCAGAAAGCAGGCAGCGGGGAAGGUCCUGGGAAAGCUGGCAGCGAGGGUUUGCAGCAGGUUGUCGGCAUGAAGAAAUCAGGUGGUGGCGACUCAGAGCGGGCCGCUGCGUUAAGCCCGGAGGACGAGACGUGGGAGGUGCUGGAGGAGGCGCCGCCGCCAGUGUUCCCCCUACGGCCUGGCGGACUCCCAGGGCUAUGCGAAUGGCUGCGGCGAGCGCUCCCCCCAGCCCAGGCAGGGGCACUGCUGCUGGCGUUGCCACCAGCAUCUCCCAGCGCUGCCCGAACCAAGGCUGCGGCGUUGCGAGCCGGGGCGUGGAGGCCAGCUCUGCUGGCUAGUCUGGCGGCGGCGGCGGCACCACUCCCAGGGCUGGGCUGGGCAUGCGACGUGGCACUUCUGCGGGGUCAGCUGGCGGAGUGGCGACGGGGCCUGGGGCUGGAACCCACGGCACUGGCUCGACGUGAGCGUGCCCUGGGCCUGGCUUCUGGAGAGCUGGCAGCGCGCGCUCAUUUCCCAGGCCCGGUGACGCGCGCCGAGGUGGAAGCAAGACUGGGCGCCUGGGCGGGCGAGGGCACUGCUGGGGGCGCAGCACUGGGGGCUCUCUCCUUCCUGUGGCCUGCGGGUGGUGCAGCGGCGACAGGUGGCCUGGGCUACCGAGCGGCUCACGGCGUCCUGCUGCAGGCUCUCGAUGAGAUGCGGGCUGAUGCUGAGGCUGUGCUGGCACCCCCUGAGCCUGCCCAGUGAGGAGUGGGAGGGGGCUUGGGAGUCCAGACUCUGACAGGGGAUGCCUGGGCUUAAUCCUGGGUGCUUGAAGGGGAUGUGGACUCUUGACUUCCAGCUGGGAUGUGUGACUUCUUAUCACCUGGAUUCAGAGAGUCUGGGGGACAGGAAUCCUGAUUUUUUUUUUUUUUUUUCUUUUUUUUGUGAGACGAAGUCUCUUGUUGCCCAGGCUGGAGUGCAAUGGCGCGACCUCGGCUCACUGCAACCUCCGCCUCCCGGGUUCAAGCGAUUCUCCUGCCUCAGCGUCCGGAGUAGCUGGGAUUACAGGUGCCUGCCACCACACCUGGCUAAUUUUUGUAUUUUUAGUAGAGACGGGGUUUCACCAUGUUGGCCAGGCUGGCCUCGAACUCCUGACCUCAGGCGAUCGACCCGCUCCGGCCUCCCAAAGUGCUAGGAUUACAGGCGUGAGCCACCGCCCCUGGCCAGGAAUCCUGAUACCUUUGGGAACCAUGGUGAAUGACAUCUAGACCCUUCUGUCCUGAAGGGAGUUGGUGGCCCAGACUCUAGCAGGGACUAUGUCUUUGUCUCCUAGGGAGUAGAAACUGGAGUUACUGGAUGUUUAGUCCUCCAGGGAGGCUGGUAGAAGUCCUGUUUCCUAAUUGGUGGGGAGGUGUCCAUGACUGGGACCUGAACUCCAGUAUAGGGGAGGGAGACCUGAGCGCCCCAGGGAGCUGGAACUCUUGGGCUUCAGAGCCUCAGAGGGAAACAGGGUCUACAUUUCUCUGGGAGAAAAAGCCUGCACACAGGUCCCCAAGGAGCAGUGGGCUUUGAAUCUUGAUGGGGUGGCGGAGGCCCCUGGGGUCUGAGACUUCCGGGGUUCUAAGAUGGCUGUGGACCUUGGUUCCUAAAUAUUGGGUAAGGGGAGGUCUGCAUCUGGAGGAGGGAUCGGGGGCUUGUGCGAGAAAGCUGGAGACUUCUUGAUCUCUCCUGGGGAGUGGAUGGGUUUCUAUAAUUGCCCUCCAAAAGCAUGUAGGGAGGGUGGUCCCACAAAAAUGAGGUGAGGUGGGUAAGAGGUCUGGGCAUGGUGGGCUCUGGGAGUAGCCAGGGACCAGGAAUGAGGUCUUUUGGGUGUGGAAGGGCAGUAAAGCAUACCUCAGAGACAGCUCCUCCAAACCUUGUAUUGGGAUCCCGGCAACUGCCUCUGUGAGUGUGACUGGGAAGGGAUAUGACUGCCUUCAUCUUCUAGGUGCUGAGCAAUUCAGGUGAUCUCUGGGGAGUCUGUUUCUCUGUCUCUUUUCUUUAGGAGUUUCUAUCUUUUUUUGGCCUUUUUCUCCUGGUAUUUAACCAUAACCCUUUAUGGCCUUGGUGUUUUGUGCACCUUCCUUUUCAGAAGAGCAGCUGUACUGCUGCACUGGUCCAAACACUUCUGUAUGGACACCUCGGGUAUCCCCAAGAGGCUCUGCUUUCUGAUGUACAUAGAGGGUGCUGCAUUGAGCCAGGGGCCCACCAAAUGGGUGGUCAGGCACUUGAGACCAUGGGAAUAUGCCAGGAGUGAAUGAAGCAAAGGCAGAAACCACAGUGCCUGGAAUGUUCUAGGCUGCUAGCCACAUGUGGGGGAAAAGUUGCAGGUUACAGAAUUCUUCAGUGUCAAAAACAGAAAAGGAGGAUCUGAGAAUCCAAGCGAUAGAAUCCCUUUUGUCGUAGACAGAAAGAGCAAAGUCCAGAGAGGGCAGGCUUGAGGCCCAACAGCACACAGUAAGGCCCUGUGGGUCUGGCCCUUGCCUAUUCUCAUUCACUGCCCCUUCCCACUCCUGUCCAGCCUGAUAGACUUUCCUUCUUUUUUUUUUUGAAAUGGAGUCUCACCUUGUCACCCAGUCUGGAGUACAGGGAUGUGAUGACUGUAGCUGAGAUGACAGGCAUGUGCCACCACACCUGGCUAAUUUUUGUAGUUUAGUAGAGAAGGGAUUUCACCCUGUUGGUCAGGCUGGUCUCGAACUCCUGACCUCAGGUGAUCCACCCGACUCAGACUCCCAAAGUGCUGGGAUUACAGGUGUGAGCCAUCAUGGCCGCCUGACUCUUUCUGAUGCCUGAGUGGCUACCUUGAGUCCUGCCUGGGGACCCAUGCACCUGCUGUUCUCUUUCCUUCAAGGCUCUACUCACAACUUCCUGUUCUACUCUCAAACCUUCCUGUGACGGGCUCAGUCAGAUCUCAGCUCACGUAUCCCCUCAGAGAGGACUUCCCCUCCCUGACCACCCUAUCUGAAGUAGCUCACAUUCCCCCACUAUUCAUUUCGGCCAGUUGAGUUUCCUUGUAGCAAUUAUUACUGUCAAAAAUGAUCUUAUUUAUUUACCUGUUUAUUGGCUUUUGACCCGUUGCCUGUCCUGUUCUCUGUUGUUUCCCCAGCAUCUAGAACAAUAGGUGCCUGACACAAUAGGUGCUUCGUAAAUAUUUAUUAUUAUUAUUAUUAUUUUAGAGACAGGGUCUUGCUCUGUUGCCCCGGCUGGAAUACAGUGGGAUGAUCAUGGCUCACUGCCAUCUCCAACUCCUGGGCUCAAACGAUCCUCCCACCUCCGCCUACAGAGUAGCUGGGACUAUAGGUACACAGCACCAAAUUUUCUGUAGAGACGGGGGUCUUGCUUUGUAGCCCACACUAGUGUUGAACUCCUGGCCUCAAGUGAUCCUCCUGCCUUGAUGGGAUUACAGGUGUGAGCCACCACACCCAGCCUAAAUGUUUAUUUCAUUGGUCAGUGUCAGAACUAGGAUUGGAAUUUAGAUUGUUAAUCUCUUGCCACAAGAUAGGAAAAUGGAGCAAGAUGAGGAGAAAAAAGCAUUUAAUGGGAGAGAACACCCUUGUCUGAGGUCAGGGACCUGGGAAGCAAGCACGACUUUGCCACUGUCACUGUGUGUUACUUGGACAGUGCCUUAUUUUCCCAUCUGUGAAAUAAAAGAGCUGGAUAAGAACCUUAGUUUUGAGAUCCUGUCUCCCUUAAAAGCUGAAGACAAAGGUAACUGAUCCAAGGGCAGACAAGGGAUGGUACCAUCAUCUCCAGCUUGGACUCCCACUGCUGACAAAAUUUGUCCCUUCAAAGUUGAGAUAGCUACCAUGGGGAAGAGCACUUAGUUCUAUACUGAAUGGCUCCAGGCAUUUUCAUGAAAGCUCUUUCAGCUUUGGGGAAGAAUAUUCAUCCAUAUCUUUACCCCAUCAUAUUAGUGUCUAAGCCCUGCAAUCAGGCAUGUCAGCCACGUGAUGGAAUGGGAGGGCUGCAGGGCAGCACUGUCCAGUAGAAACGAAAUGCAAGCCACAUAUGUCAUUUUAAGUUUUCUUUUUUUGAGAUGGAGUUUCACUCCAUCACCCAGGCUGGAGUGCAGUGGCACGAUCUCGCCUCACUGCAACCUCCGCCUCCCAGGUUCAUGUGAUUCUCCUGCCUCAGCCUCCUGAGUAGCUGGGAUUACAGGCAUAUGCCACCAUGCCUGGCUAAUUUUUGUAUUUUUAGUAGAGAUGGGGUUUCACCAUGUUGAUCAGGCUGGUCUGGAACUACUGACCUCAGGCCACCCGCCUUGGCCUCCCAAAGUGCUGGGAUUACAGGCAUGAGCCACCGCGCCCAGCUAAUUUUUGUAUUUUUAUUUUAUUUAUUUAUUUAUUUUUUGGGAGACGGAGUCUUGCUCUGUCACCCAGGCUGGAGUGCAGUUGUGCGAUCUUGGCUCACUGCAACCUCAGCCUCCCAAGUAGCUGGGAUUACAGGCAUGCACCAUCAUGCCCAGCUAAUUUUUGUAUUUUUAGUAGAGAUGGGGUUUCACUGUGUUGGCCAGGCUGGUCUUGAACUCCUGACCUCAGGUGAUCCACCGGCCUCAGCCUCCCAAAGUGCUGGGAUUAUAGGCGUGAGCCACUGCACCCGUCCUAAUUUUUGUAUUUUUAGUAGAGAUGGGGUUUCACCAUGUUGGCUAAGCUGGUCUGGAACUCAUGGCCUCAAGUUAUCUGCCCACCUCAGCCUCCCAAAGUGCUGAGUAAGCCAAGUUUUCUAAUAGCCACAUUAGACAAGUAAAAGGAAACAGGUUAAAUUCAUUUUAACAUGUUUUACUUAACCCAAUGUAUCCAAAAUAGCAUUUCAACAUGUCAUCGGUUUUUUAGUUUUUUUUUUUUUUGAGAUAGUGCUUCGCUUUGUUGCCCAGGCUGGAGUGCAGUGGCACAAUCUCGGCUCACUGCAACCUCCACCUUCCAGGUUCAAGUGAUUCUCCUGCCUCAGCCUCCCGAGUAGCUGGGAUUACAGGCACCCGCCACCAUGCCCACUAAUUUUUGUAUUUUUGGUUAGAGAUGGGGUUUCGCCAUGUUGGCCAGGCUAGUCUCAAACUCCUGACCUCAGGUGAUCCACCCACCUCGGCCUCCCAAAGUGCUAGGAUUACAGGCGUGAGGCACCGUGCCUGGCGUCAUCGGUAUUAUUUAAAUGAAUUAUGUUACGUUCUUUUGUGCUGUCUUCAAAAUCUGUUAUAUAUUUUACACUUACACCAAAUCUCAAUUACCAUGGUACAUUUUUAUCUGAAAUGCUUGACCUUUAUUUUGAUUUCAUAAAAUUCAUAGUUGGAGAAGUAGAUUCACAUAUCCAAGUUGUUCCAAUUAUAUAAUAGUUUUCCAAAAACUGAGAUGGGUGUCCAUUUUUUUUUUAAGUAAAGAUGCAGGUCUGGUUAUGUUGACCAAGUUGCUGGGUUGUUUUGUUUUGUUUUGAGACAGAGUCUCACUUUGUCACCCAGGCUGGAGUGCAGUGGCAUGACCUCAGCUCACUGCAACCUCUGCCUCCCAGGUUCAACUGAUUCUCUUGCAUCAUCCUCCUGAGUAGCUGGGACUACAGGUGUAUGCCACCAUGCCUGGCUAAUUUUGGUAUUUUUCUCAGAGACGGGGUUUCACCAUGUUGGGCAUGCUGGUCUUGAACUGCUGACCUCAGGUGAUCCGCCCACCUCGGCCUCCCAAAGUGCUGGUAUUACAGGCAUGGGCCACCACACCUGGCCUCAGCUGUUCAAUUAAAAGUAAAUACAACUUAAAAUUCUAUGUUUCAUUGGCAGUAGUGCAACAUUAAUACUGAGUAGCCACAUGUGAUUAGUGGCUAUGGUAUUGGACAGGGAAGGUACAGAAUACUUCCAUCAACAUAGAAAAUUCUAUCAGUCUAGCUCUAGGGGCAGAUAGUCCUUCCACUGACUUGGGCAAGUCACUCUACAAAUGGCAUCUACCUCACAUGGUUAUGGUGAGAAUUCAGCGUAUGUAUGUACAUGCAGGCACACAAUAUGCACACAGACACAUAACAUAGUACACCCUUUCCUGAAAAGCCUGACACAUGGAGCUCAAACAUGAGUGCCACCCACCCCUGGGCAGCACCAAGAUGGCUCUAGUCUGGGUGCCUUUGUCUCACCCCCAUGCCUUUGCUCGGAGUGUGCUCCUCAUUUUUCUGCCACUUUGACCCUGUCUCUGAUUUGGUCCUGUCUGACAUCACUGCUAUAUGCUUUGCUCCUCUCAAUUUCCUCUGCCCUCAUGCCAGCAGGAGUCAUGCCAGAGAUCAUAUCUGAGAAAGCAAGACAAUUUUGUGUGUGUGUCUGUGCCCAUAGAGGAGUGCUGGUUGUGUUGAUAUAGUUGUAGAUUGGUUGUGUUUACACAGUUGUAUAUAUUGACACCCUUGAGUGUUAUGACUUCUUUUGGGGGUGGUCGCCUUUUAAAUCAUAACUUUUAAUGGGAUUCCAUUUUAGUCUUUGUGAAGACAUAAGGUUGUUGGCAGGCAUCUGUCCCUGGGAGCAUCCAAGCAGAAAAGACUAAGACUCCCUUGUAGACAGAUCACUGGCCGCCACUGAAGUGUGUCUGCAUGGCACCACAGGGCUGGAAGACCCUUGAAGGCAGGAAUUCAAGGAAAUGUAUGAUGAAUUUUGGCAUUGCCAUCAAAAGCAGAACAGGCAUGGAAAACUUGGGUGAGUGGGCGAGACAACCUCCUCACCACAGCAGAGUUCCAUCCAUGCCUGGAUAAUGAUGGAGGGAUUUGUGUCCACUGCAGUGGGGAACCAUGAAGGACACAUCAAGGGUGUGGUUGGCCUGUGGUGCUCUUUGGAGGAAUGAAUAAAAAUGAAUAGAAAUCCUAUUGCGUGUCUGUUCUUUUGGAGUUUGAGGGAAAAGAAAGAUCCUUGAGAUUUUGACUGGGCUGGAAACCUAGACUCCAGCGUCUGGGGAUAGGAGGGAUGGUGGGGAAUCCGCUGGGAAAAACUGGGCUGUGAUCAAGAGAAUUUAUCAGUAUCUGAGUUUUUCCACCCUGGAAGGAGUGCGGGCAGACUUACUGUUUAAACAUUGGGAGCUUAUGAUGGUAAAGCGCCUUAGUUCUGGAGCCAGGUAUACCCAUUAAUGACCCCAACUGGGCCAGCCUUUCUGUAGCCAUGCCCUUGGAUUGUUGCUCUCCUUCUAGGUUUGACUAUGUGGUUUGCUUCAGCCACUAGAACAAUAGCAAACAUGAUACAAGCAGAGGCUUGGAAAGUGCUUAUGCGGCCGGGUGUGGUGGCUCACACCUAUAAUCCCAGCACUUUGGGAGGCCAGGGCGGGCAGAUCACAAGGUCAGGAGAUCGAGACCAUCCUGGCUAACACAGUGAAACCCCGUCUCUCUACUAAAAAUACAAAAAAUUAGCUGGGUGUGGUGGUGCACACCUGUAGUCCCAGCUACUCGGGAGGCUGAGGCAGGAGAAUAGCUUGAACCUGGGAGGCGGAGGUUGUAGUGAGCUGAGACUGCGCCGCUGCACUCCAGCCUGGGCAACAGAGCGAGACUUCUCUCAAAAAAAAAAAACCAAAGUGCUUAUGCACUGGGACUUCCUCUCUUGCUCCCCUUGGGACCCCUACCACCACUGCCACAUCCAAACCCCGGGCUGGCUGAGCAUGGUGGCAUAUGGGUAUAAACCCAUAAUCCCAGCACUUAGGGAGGCAAAGGUGGAAGAAUUUCAUGAGCCCAGGAGAUCGAGACUAGCCUGAGCAACAUGGCAAGACCCCCAUCUCUACAAAAAAGCAACAACAACAGAAUUAGCCAGAUGUGGUGGUGUGCACCUGUGGUCCCAACUACAUGGGGGAGGCUGAGGCAAGUGGAUUGUUUGAGCCCAGGAAGUCGAGGCUGAAGUGAGCUAUGAUGGCUCCACUGCACUCCAGCCUGGGUGACAGAGCAAGACAAUGUCUAAAAAAAUAAAAAGAAGGAAAGAAAAGGAAAAGAUCUGGGCUAACCUGCUGGGUAAUAAAGGGAAAAGAGACACAUGGCUCCGUCAUCCUUGAUCCCUGCCACCCAUAGCCAACCAACCUCUGAAACAGAGCUCCCUAGCUGAUAGGCAGCUGAACCCAGCUGAGACCAGCAAAAGAACUGCCCAGCUGAUCCCAGACCAAGUUGCAACCCAGAGAAUCAUUAACUAAAUAGGUGAUUGUUCUAAACCACUAAAUUUUGGAGUGGUUUGUUAUGUAGCAAAAGCAACUAAUACAGACUUGUUCUCUCUGUGUGUGAUGUGGUCUCUUUCUCCCCAACAACAUGACCCAAUGAUUAAAAUCUUAAAUUCUGCCACUUUUUAGCUGUGUGACUGCCAAUGUGACAGCCUUCUGAGCCUCUGAUGUCUCCUGAAAACAGAGAUGUGAAUAAUAGUGCCUAUGACAUAGAGUUGUGAAAAUAAAAUGAAAAACAGCUUCUUAA